AUGGAGGAUUUGUAUUUCUUUCAUCCAGGUGCCUGGUGAUAGGGAUUGUCUGAUUAACUAUCCUUUUCUUAGUGUGAUUUGAGAUUUUCUAAGCCACCUUGAUUACUCAAAGCUGGACUGCAGACCAUAAAGGAACUGACUUAAUUCUGGGUUACUUUUGCUCCCAGGAUAUAGCCUUUCUGAAUUCUAACUCAAUCAGGGUCUUUACCUUUGUUGGAACCCUAGAUUUGGACUUUUUUAGAUCUAUUCUGUAGAAGCCACCAAGUCUAUUUCUUGGCCUUUCAACCCCAGGACAAAAGUAGCUGACAGUGCUUUGCUUAUUUCUCUCCCUGGGUUUCUCACCUUUUCAGGUCUUGGCUCAGUAGUUCUUGUCUGUUUUAUUAGUACAUGGCUUAAAACCCCCAAACUUAAAGUAUAUCUUAUCUAUAUAUAUAUUUUUUUUCGAGACAGAGUCUUGCUCUGUCGCCCAGGCUGGAGUGCAAUGGUGUGAUCUUGGCUUACUGCAACCUCCGCCUCCUGGGUUCAAGCCAUUCUCCUGCCUCAGACUCUCGAGUAGCUGGAAUUACAGGCGCCUGCCACCAUGCCCAGCUAAUUUUUGUAUUUUUUAGUAGAGAUGAGGUUUCACCAUGUUGGUCAGGCUGGUCUCGAACUCCUGACCUCAGGUGAUUGACCCUCCUCGGCCUCCCAAAGUACUAGGAUUACAGACAGGAGUCACUGUGUCUGGUCCUUAUCUAGAUUUUUUUUUUUUUUUUUGAGAUGGAGUCUCACUCUGUUGCCCAGGUUGGAGUGCAGUGGUGUGAUCUUGGCUCACUGCCACCUCCGUCUCCUGGGUUCAGGCGAUUCUCCUGCCUCAGCCUUCUGAGUAGCUGGGGCUACAGGCGCGUGCCACCAUGCCUGGCUAAUUUUUGUAUUUUUGGUACAGACAGAGUUUCACUAUAUUGGCCAGGCUGGUCUCGAACUCCUGACCUCGUGAUCCCCUGCCUCGGCCUCCCAAAAUGCUGGGAUUACAGGCAUGAACCACCAUGCCAGGCCCCUUAUCUAGAUUUUUAAUGGUCAUGGGAAUGUUUGAUGCUGUUCUCAAAUAUACGGGAAGCAGAAACCCCCCCCACAUGAUAUUUUAAUUAUUUGUUUAUAUGUCUGUCCUUUCAGUAGGGUGGCCUUUUAAAUUUAUUUUUAGUAUUUCUCUGCUGUAAGCCUUUUAUUGUUUGUAACUCAGCACCUGAUAAUGUCUGAUACAUAAGUGCAUAGAAAAUAUUAACUGGUUUUGGCAUGGCUUUAAGAAAAAAUUGUGAAGGUAUCCUUUCCUUUGAGCCAUAAAGGAAAAUUGAGAUUAAAUCUAAUUGUUUUAUUUGUUGUACCUUCAGUACCAGACAUAAUAAAUUUGGAUGUUAGUGGCAGUGGAAAAUCAUGGGAUAAUUUCUGAAUAACCACUUAGUGCCUCUUAAAUGUGGUUAAAGGGAAGAUUAAUUUCAAAACUGUAUGCAGGAUAGAUGAGAUAUUUUGUCAGGAUGCAUUUUAUAAGUAUUCUAUAGUAUGGUAAUUUUUAAAGUGUGGUCCCCAGACCAGGUAGCAUUGGCAUUACUUGGGAUUUUGUUUGAAAUGCAAAUUAUCUGAUCCUGCCUCAGAUCUUCUGAAUGAGAAACUAUAGUAGUAUGGCUAAGCAGUUUGCUUUAAAAGCCCUCAAUUAGGUUCUGAUGCAUACCUAAAUUAUUGAGCUACUGCUGUAACACAAUAAAACAGAAUAUGAUUUUGAUUUAGGCCCCUUAAAAGCUAAAGGUUAUUUAUCUUUCUAUGAUGAGAAUAUUUUUGGAAAAUAUUUAAUGCAGUCUCAAUGUUGAUCUUUCUUUAGAAUUAAGUUUUAAGCCUCUAUAAAGUCAUUAGGUUUAUUAGAGCAAAAUUAUGACCUGAAAUAGUUGAGUUCGUUGAAAAAUAAAAACUUGUCUAUGUUACACAGGAAAAUGAUACCAGUCUAAUUGUUGACAAUAACUGGCUUAUUCCAGUUGCCUUGCAGUGUUCCUUAAGGGAGUGGAUUGUUUAGGACCUAACUUUCUUAAUACAAGUUUCAUUAGAAGUAAAUUCUCUAUUUUUUCAUUGUUUGGAAGGAAAUAUUUAACAUAUACAAUAUGAUGGAACUUCUGUAGAAUAUAGCAUAAUCACAGAGACAGUUGUAUCCAUCCAUUUCCUAGUCAGUUUCACCAUAUUUUUAAAUGAGGCACAAGAUUACUGUGUUAUCAAAAUGUUAACAUUAAGCUUUUUAACAAGUCUGUGUAGUCACUUGAUUUUUCAGAUUUUGCCCACUAAUUUUAUGAGGGCCAUUGGGCAAAGUGUUUUAAUCCAGAAUUUAAAAUUGUUCAUUUGUAAUUGGGCAGGCUUAUAAAAAGGGGCAUAUUUUAAAUCUUUAUCAUCACUUUAUAGCCAUAAUAUACAUACUAAAAGUUUGGUAGCAAUUUGAGUAUUUAACUACAUAGGGUGGUACUUUGAAGGAAAAAGCAUUUUAAGUUGAGCUUUAAUUUAAUUUCUGCUUUUAAAAACCCAAUAUAGUAGUACGUCAUCUAUGUAUGUACAUUGAGCAUGCUUCUUAACAUAUUUAACUUCCAAUUCUUUGAUAACCGGUUGCAUUCAAUUACUUGUUUAAAUAAUUGGGCAAGUUUCCUGAGUUGUAGGCUGUGAAAUAUUUUCAAGAUGGUUUGGGUAAAAAAUUUUUUCAAAGUAGGUGCCGUCAGUGACUUUGAUCACAGAGAAAUCAGUAUGAUCCUGUGACAAGUUUAGUUUUAACAAUGUAACUUCUUGUGUAAACUCAGUCACCUAGUAAUGUGAAUUAGUUGCAAAGUGAUUCUGUAUUCUUAGUGACCCACUGUUAGAUGUUUUCAGACUAGUAAAUGAUAAAUAUUUAUUGUUAAAAUCAUCCUUAAAAUUUUAUUUGAACAUGCAGCACUUUUUGCAGUGUGAAAUUGAAAAAUCAAUUGUUUAGUUUUUACCAAAGGAAAAUUAGAGUUUUGUAUACAUAUUUGAUGAAUACAGUAAACAGGUUAAAAUUUAGCAAAUAGAAUUUUGUAAGCAUUUUUAAAAUGUGUGAAUUCUGUGAUAAGGGGGUGGCUUUGCUACAAUUUAUUACAAAGCUAAGUUAUAUUUCAUUACUUAUGUAAAAUAGUGUUCUUUGUUUAGCUUCUUAAAGUGGUAGGAGAAUUGUAUAAUUCCAUUGAUUGGUUCCAUGCAGUGGAAAUCUGACCUUUAGCAGAUGUUUGAGAAAUUGCCAGCACAGCAUGAUCAGCCAAAAAGACAGUUUUCCCCUUGUUACUUGACAGGCCUUUCAUGCUUUAGUAACAUGCCAAAGAAAUGUUUAAAUUAUUUUUUUAUAAUAUCACAUGCUCUCUAAAAUAUUAAGAAUACAUUGAAAAACAUGCAUAAAAUGAGAUAGAUUUUUCCUGCAAUUACGGAUUGCAAUUCAGCUGACUUUUAAAUGUUUAUUAUUAAAAAAAAAAAACUAAGAUAAAUGCUGAUUGUUUUGUGAAUUAUGUGUUACUUUGAGAUUUAAAAUGUCUUCGGCUAUGUAGUUAAUUGUUAUUAGGGUUUGAUGUGUGUUAUUUUUUCCAUGAUCAUGUUUUCCAUGAUCAUGUAUAACAAUUUAAACACUGUUAUAAGUUUCUCUUAUUUUAGUGUUAUUUAAUCGCAAGUAUCGUCUUUGGUUGGCUUUUUUAUUUUUUAAUAGAGGCUUUUUGAUAGGGGUUAAAUGCAUCACAGAGAAGUUAUCCUAUCUGGAACUUCUCGCUAAGGGCAGGAUACUGCAUGAAUCCACUUUAAAGCCUCUUCUCUGAAGGACAGUAUUUCUUUAGAGAAUGAAAUGGGUUCAGCUGUGUAGUUGUGGGGGUUCAGCUGUGUAGUUGUGGGAGUUCAGCAAAAACACUGUAAGCUCUGUUUUCUUCAACUUCAUGGAUUGAGCGUACAGGAAGGGGAAGGAGUUGCCUUAAUGUUUAAGAAUGAAGUGAUGAAUUGAUAGUAUCAGCAGUUGCCAGACUGUAUCUUUUUCUGCAGGUGCUUAUUUUCUGUAGGGCAUUGCAGUUGUUUUUCAUUGUGUUAGGUUAUGAGACGAUUUUAAGGAAAAUUUAAGGAACAUGAUCUUACAUAGUUUCAUUUUACAGUUUUGUAACUGUUUUGUAUGUCUUAGGUUUAUAUACUGAAUUAGUUCUUCCAGAGGAUUAUGAUUGAAAGUUUUGGCUGUGUGUACCUAUCACCUUACAAAAAUAAAAAGAUUUUUUUAAAGGUCAUGUUCAGUAUCAGUAGUUCUAAGAAUAUGCUAAAUUAAAAUUUAAAAAUCAAACACCUAUAAUAAAGUUUUGCUGAAUCCACAUGAAUUGAACUAAUGGUUUGUAAUACCAGUUAUAUUACAAGUGAGAACUAGUUUCAUAUUUUGAUAUAUAAAAGCUUUGAAGGAAGCAUAAUUGAUAACUGUUUAUUAAUAUCACAUAAUAGUUAAUCUUUCAUAUUGGUACUUUCUGAUAAGGUUUUAUUAGAUGGAGAAGGGUUAUAUAAUUUAGUAAACUGGCAGCUUUUAAAUGAAUAAUGACACUAAAAUUUAAAGAUUUAAUCAUAAUGAGGUAUAUCUGAUACGUAGUACCUGUGAUAUUAUAUAUUAAUAGUAAAGUCAUUUUAUAUAAGGAAAAAUUUUAUUCUUAAGUGGGGUUUUCUAAGUAACUAUAUGUUUACACAAAGUCAUACUGUUAACAUUUAGUCACUUCCAGAGUCAGUGGAGUUGUAUCCUGAAGAGGAUUAAAUUGCAAAGUUGGCACAGCACAUAAAGCAAAAAUGCACUUAAAUUCAGUUCACUUUUAAGGCCUUGUUGGGAAUACCAACCUAUUGUUUGUCAGUUCAUCCAGGACAGUUUUUUUUUUUUCUCUAGUGUUGGAAUAAUUUUUUUUUUUUUUUGAGAUAGAGUCUUGCUGUAUCGCCCAGGCUGGAGUGCAGUGGCCUGAUCUCAGCUCACUGCAGCCUCUGCCUCCUGGGUUCAAGUGAUUCUCCUGUCUCAGCCACCCGAGUAGCUGGGUCUACAGGCACCUGCCACCACAACCGGUGAGUUUUGUUGUUGUUGUUGUUGUUAUUUUUAGCAAAGAAAGAUGAAGUUUCACCAUGUUGGCCAGGCUGGUCUUGAAUUCCUGACCUCAAGUGAUUCACCCUCCUCAGCCUCCCAAAGUGUUGGGAUUACAGGCAUCAUCUACUGUGCCCGGAGCAGAAUAAAUUUUUAAUAUAUAUUUUGAUAGGCUGAUUUUCUUGCAUCUCGAUUUUUCUUGUAUGUCAGUAACUGGAAUCACAGUUACCUUUUGAGCACGGUGCUCACAUUAUGAGAGUUGAGAAAAUUACGGGGAACAAACUCUGGCCUUAUGGUGAUUCUGGUUAGACUUGAGAUCUCUAAAUUGAUAUUUUUAAAUGAGAAUAUAUAAUACACAGACUAAAAUAUACAUUUUAAGGUUAAAAAAAGAGAAACUGUUUACUAAGAAUGUUUAGUAGAUUCAGUUUUCUUAGUGUUUAAUACUAGAAAAUACACAGUAUUGGCUGGGUGCGUGGCUCAUGCCUGUGAUCCCAGCACUUUGGGAGGCCGAGGCAGGCAGAUCACGAGGUCAGGAGAUCGAGACCAUCCUGGUUAACACAGUAAAACCCUGUCUGUACUAAAAAUACAAAAAAUUAGCUGGGCGUGUUGGCGGACACCUGCAGUCCCAGCUACUCGGGAGGCUGAGGCAGGAGAAUGGCAUGAACCCAGGAGGUGGGGCUUGCAGUGAGCCAAGAUCGCACCACUGCACUCCAGCCUGGUCGACAGUGCAAGACUCCGUGUCAAAAAAAAAAAAAAAAAAAGUAUUGAUAGCAUACUUUUAAGAAAUCCAAAUGUCUUUGUAAAAGUAGGUAUUUUUCAUUCUUUCAGUAUCAGUUACUCUUCACUAUGGUUCUUUUUCACAUUUAAAUAGAAUCAAGGAACCUUUUAUCUUUGGUUUAUCUGGUAUUUUUCAGUGUUAGCAAUUUUGAAAUUCUCUAAUUUUUACCACAAACAUUUUUGACUCUUUCAUUCAGCUUAUAAUCUGAAUUGACAGAAAAAUCCAGGGAGAAAAGUUAAAAUACUUCCUAAAGUUAAAAUAUUUGCUUUAUUUAGAUUUCUAGUAUUUCUUAUCAAGGAAAAAAAUACUUUUUCAUUAUCUUAUCGCUUGAUAACCGUUUUUUGUCUCAGCUAAACGGAAGAAAAGUUACCUGGCAGCAUAAGAUAGCUAUGAAGAAUCUUUCCCCCACCAGAAAGAAGUUUAGCAAACUAUUUUACUGAAUAAAUCUAAGACUUCCUCCUUCCCAGUAGUUGCCCACAAUUUUCCUCCAAUAUGAGAUUAUGUCUCUAUUUUGUAAUUCUGCUCAGAAAACCUGUCUUAAAAUCUACACAUAUUAAACUAUAAUAUGUCAUAAAUUUUAAGAAUGUUAUUUAACAGAGGUAAAUUUAUCAUGAAUACCAUAUAUUUAAGGUAGCAAAACAUAAAGAGAGUAAUAACCUCUUUUGAUACUCAACAGCAGACCAGGUAAAGUCCAAACAGUUCUGUCUCAUCAAAAUAAUGAAGGUUGCUUGUCUUUGACCUCUUUUCCUGUUACCUCUUUAAGAGAUAACACACAUAUACAUACGCUUUUGUAGAUGAGACCAUUCUAAAAUUUAUAAAUUGUGUUGUAUAUCUUUGUCUGCCUGAUUAAAAUGGCUUGUCUUAAGGUAACACUGAACUGCUUAGUCUUUCAAUAGGAAUUUAUUUAGCAACUACUUUGUGGUAUUGUUUUGAUAUACUCUAUUUUUGUGUUUCGGCUUUUUCUUAUUUAUUUUAAUUAAAUCAAUAUCAUCCCUCGUAUACACUAUUCUUCUGUGCAGUUGACACUUGAACAAUGUGGGUUUGAACUUUGAGAGUCAAUUUAUAUGCAGAUACUUUUAAAUAAAUAUAUUGCAAAAUAUUUUAGAGAUUUGCAGCAAUUUGAAAAAACUCAUAGAUGAACCAUGUAGCCUAGAAAUAUUUUUAAAAAUUUAGAAAAUGUUAGGUAUGUCAUAAAUGCAUAAAAUAUAUGUACAUCUUAGUUUUAUCAUUUGCUACCAUAAAAUAUACACAAAUCUAUUUAAAAAGUUAAAAUAUCAGAACUUUACCCACACAGAGACGUGACAUGGCACUAUUUACAGUAGAGAGAAAUAUAAACAAACAUAAAGAUGCAGUAUUAACUCAUAACUACAUAAAAUUAACUUUAGUACAUGCUGUGAUAGGUUUUUAGCCACCUCCUGUUUUUACUGUGUUGAACUCAAAUGUUGCGAAUGUCUGCUUAAAACUCAGUGUGAUGCUGACAUCUCCAUGUGAGUAGUUGACCUCUCCACUAAAUACCAUAUUGCAAUAAGAAAUGAUCUCUCGCAGUCCUUGCAUAAUUUUUAAUGUUGUUUAGUGCAAUCUCGCAAACUUCGAAUGAUACCAUAGAACAGAAAUUUAGGAAUCAAUAAGUACAGUACUGUAAAUGUAUUUUCUCUUGCUCAUAAUAACUUCUCUAGCUUACUUUACUGUAAGAAUACAGUAUAUAAUAGACAUACAAAAUAUUUGUUAAUUGACUUUAUGUCAUUGUUAAGACUUCCGGUCAACAGUAGGCUAUUACCAGUUAAUUUUAUGGGGAGUCAAAAAUUACAUUCAGCUUUUCGACUGGGCGGGCUGUCCUCAGUCCCAACCCCUGAAUUGUUCCAGGGUCAGUUGUACAUAGCUCUUCAUGUUUUUAAAAAACACAUUUUUGGCUGGGCAUGGUGGUUCAAGCCUGUAAUCCCAGCACUUUGGGAGGCUGAGGUGGGCAAAUAGCUGGAGCUCAGGAGUUCUCAGGAGUUCAAGAGCAGUCUGGGCAACAUGGCCAAGAUCUUGUCUCUAUUUAAAAAAAAAAAAAAAAAAAAAAAUUGGGCCAGGCGCUGUGGCUUACGCCUGUAAUCCCAGCACUUUGGGAGGCCAAGGUAGGUGGGAUCAUGAGGUCAGGAGAUCGAGGCCAUACUGGCUAACAUGGUGAAACCCUGUCUCUACUAAAAAUACAAAAACUUAGCUGGGCAUGGUGGCACGCACCUGUAGUCCCAGCUACUUAGGAGGCUGAGGCAGGAGAAUCACUUGAACCCAGGAGUUGGAGGUUACAGUGAGCCAAAGUUGUGCCACUGCACUCCAGCCUGGACAACAGAGUAACACUCCGCCUCAAAAAAAAAAAAAAAAAAAUCAGGCCGAGUGUGGUGGCUCACGCCUGUAAUCCCAGCACUCUGGGAGGCCCAGGCAGGCGGAUCACCUGAGGUCAGGAGUUCGAGACCAGCCUGACCAACAUGGUGAAAACUCGUUUCUACUAAAAGUACAAAAAUUAGCCGGACAUGGUGGUGGGCACCUGUAAUCCCAGCUAUUCAGGAGGCUGAGGCAGGAGAAUCGCUUGACCCCGGGAGGCGGAGGUUGCAGUGAGCCAAGAUUGGGCCACCUACUCCAGCCUGGGUGACAAGAGCGAGACUCCGUCUCAAAAAAAAAAAAAAAAAAAAAAAUCAGUGACACAUUUGUAUCUACUCAUGUAACUACCAUGUUUCUCACUCACUGUAGUUAACCUGGUACCUCUACCCAGUCUAUACCGCCCCUCUGUUCCACUGAUCUCAGUUCUAUCACCAAAGAUGAGAUUUUCCUGUUGUUGAACUUAAUAUAACUGGAAUCAUUCAGUGGCUUUUUACACUCAGUAUAAUAUCUGUGAAACUUAAUAUAUUAGAUUCCUAGGGCUGCCAUAACAUCACAACAAAUUUGGUGGAUGGAAACAACAGAAGUUUAUUCUUUCAUUGCUCUGAGGACCAAAAGUCCAAAACUUCUUCAUUAAAUGGGACAUAGACUGAUUAGUAACAAGAUUUACUUGUCUUUCUCCAUGGUUUCAACAGUGAAAAGUAGUUUUAAUGUUGACUGAAAGUUGAUUAGUGCUUAAGACCUGAAAAUGCUUAGGAUUGUUUGCUGUUGGAAGAUACGGCUCUUAUCUACUUUUCUCCAUUAGAGCUCUGGAGUUCUCUUGGGCCUAGAAAGAAGUAAUUUGGAACAGUUAGUGUAGUGUGGGGUAUUAUGAAAACCAAAAUAGAGUAUUAUAAUAAAAUAUAUAAUAAAAACAUACAUAAAAUUACUGGUUUGGGCUCAGUAUAUUUUUUGUCUUUAAAAAGAAGAUGCUAACUCAAGGAAAGGGUAAUAAGGUAUGCUGGAAAGUUUAUUUGCUUAGAAGUUAGGACUGAUUUCUGGUCCUGGCUCUGUCAUUAAUAAUUAUGUCUCUGGAUUCUUAUGGAAGGUUUUUCCAGUUCUUCAUAUGACAGCUUGGUAUUAGCAGUGGUCCUGACAUUUAUAGAUAUUAUCACUUUCUUUCACCUCACUCACUCUUCAUUUCCUUCACAGUAUUAACAGUAACCUUUUCUGUUACAUUUUGUUAACUUUAGAAAUAGUAGAUCAUGUUAGACUAAGUAGAGAUCACAAAAAGAUGAGAUUUAGGAGAAAUCCAUAGAUGUUUUGAACUGUGGAUGAAUAGUUCACCAACUAUUUCCUGUACACAAAAGCCAUGCAAUAUAUGUGAUUAAAUUUGUGCCUUGGUGAAAUAAUAUGUUAUAUGUCACUGUAUGUAUUGUGGGGUCAUUUAUAAAUGGUUACAAUAUUUUAAAGUAGGAAUACCUAGGGUCUGCUUGUCGUUAGUUUUCUGUGAUAGAUAUUCGACAGUGCUUCCUGGCAUUUAGGAAGGGGCAGUGAGAUCUUUUAAUACAUCUAGAGAAGACACUUCCUUAUAUGAUCUUUUCAUUUAUUCAAAUAUAUAUUUAUUACUUCCUCUGUGCCAGGUACUGUGUGGCUGAGCAGCCUAGACUUGAUUCUGUAAAGGAAAUUAAAAAUCCCAGGACCCCCAGACUCCUUAUGCAAAAGGAAAGUUAAUCCUGGAGUCUGAGUCAUGCAACACACUCUUUCAAUUUUGCUCCUGUGGCCCAGGCUGGAGUGCAAUGGCGCGAUCUCGGCUUACUGCAACCUUCGCCUCCCAGGUUCAAGUGAUUCUCCUGCCUCAGCCUUCCGAAUAACUGGGAUUACAGGCGCCCGCCUCCACGCCCAGCUAAUUUUUUGUAUUUUUAGUAGAGAGGGGGUUUCACCGUGUUAGCCAGGAUGGUCUUGAUCUCCUGACCUCGUGAUCCACCUGCCUCGGCCUCCCAUAGUGCUGGGAUUACAGGCAUGAGCCACUGCACCAGGUGAUUUUUAUCUGUUGUGCUUAGCUUUUGAGGAGUUGCUUUUCAGUUUUGAAAUUUAUGAGUGUUAGUUCUGAAAAGUUUUUCUGAAUUGUUUCUAAGAUUCUCUUUUUUCUCUGUUACGUUUCUCUUUUCUGAAACUUGUGUUGGGAUAUUGAACCACACUGAUUCUGUUUUUCCCUUUGUCUCCUAUAUCCUUUAUGUUCUACUUGGAAAAAUUUUCAGCUUCCUUUUCUAAACCUAUUGUAUUUUUUAUUUCUGCUAUCAUAAUUUAAUUUGCUAAAGAUUUUUUUCUGUUUUUUUUUUUGUUUGUUUCUCCAGAUUGUUGUAUUUUGAUAGCAUCCUUUUGCUUUUGAUUAUGGUAUUUUCCUCUUACCUCAUUCAGAAUAUUCUUUUUUUUUUUAAUGUUUUGUUUUCUUCUCUUUGGUCUAUUUUCUUCCUGUCAUUUUUCCCUAUGUAUAUUUUAGUCUCUGUAUUUUAUGUCUAAUGUUUUCUUCAAAUGAAAUUCCUGACAAUUCUUUCAGACUACUUGUAUGUAAUAGAGUAACACUAAAAAAGUACAUUGGAAACUCUGAGCAUGUGGGUGGACUUUGUUGGAUGUCAUCUUAUCUAUUUGAGAUCUGCUCAUUUCCAUAGGGGAAUACCUAAUGUCUGUAUAUUUAGAUUUUUUUAAAGUGGUUAGGUUUCCAAAGAAAUCUGUCAGUGCUUUAUCUGGCUUUCAGAGUUAUGCCCUAUGAGGAAAGAAGACUGAGGAUGAAAGGAGGGUCUAGUCCUAGACAUAUUUCAUUAUGUCAGCUUUCACUUAAUCCUUCUUCUGUUUCAAUGGUAAUCUCUGCCCUCAACCUGUUUUAAUAUGCUUCUUGGUCCAGGGACCCUUUCAUAACCUUUUCUAAGAAAUAAACCUUUUUUUCGUACCAUAAUGGGAAAGGAGACAGUUGCUAGGCUAGAGUCAGGGAGAAAUCUGAGAGUCUAGCUGCUGCUUCAGUAGACUAUGGUCAGUCUUCCUGUUAGCCCUACUUUACCCCUACUCAAUUUUUGAACCUUUGGGGCAUAGCUUAUCUUUGGUAAUUUAGCAUAUUAAUCAGCUUUCCCUAAUAUUUGGCUUUAGAUUAAGCUUCUUUUUUUUUCCACUAAGUUAGCUACCACUGGUUUUGCUGUUAUUUUAAAAUUAGUUUAUUUUACCCAUCUUUUCAAUCUGUUGAAACCUUACAAUCCUCAUCAUCCAGCAUGUUAAUUAUUAUUCUUUGAGUCCUACAUUCAUUUCACAAUUUGACUUUUGUAAGUGUCUUGACUGAAGUGUAAUGAUAGAGCCCUGUGGAAUAUAUUUGAAGACAUUUUAUCAAUUUUACUUUAGUUCUUGGUUAAUAUUAUAAGUUAUGGUUGUUUAUUCCAGCUAUCAGUACCUGCUUGUGCUGUAUUAUUGAGUUUUUAUUUUUUUAUUUUAUUCCUAAGAAUAUUUUCAGGAUAUUUUCCCAUACUAUUUUGCUUAAAAAAAAAUCUAGUGUUGGAUUAGUUAUACUAGCCUACCUAAAAAGAAGAAAUUUAUUGAUAAUAAAAAUUUAACAUCACUUGUAGGGAAAUAAAAUUACCUCUUGGUGUAGCCUUUUUUCUUUUUUUAUGCCUUUAAACCAUCUUACAAAUAAAAACUUCUGGACUUUGAUAUGGACACAUAUUGAUGGAUUAUUAAACUUUUACACUUGAAACUUCUGUGAUUGUUUGAUACAUAUUUUCUAGGAAACGUUUUUCUUCAUGUCCAAAAUUGCUUAUUAGAAACUGUUCUCUUCCAGUAUUGUUUUCCACACAUUGGAGAUGCAUACAUGCCUAAUUCCGACCUGUGAUUAGUUAAGCUCCACAGAAAAAAACUAAAUUUAAAAGUGACUAGAUAUUCUCUGUCUUCUUAUUUGCUCUUCAUUUACUUUUUAACUAUGUUUCUUCUACCUUUUCCAGUUUUUUAUUCAAUUCUCCUUAGUGGAGAAGAUGGAUACAAAGCAGGAGGUGUGAGUAGUUGUUUAUUUUGUCUGCAUCUGUUAAUAUUACACCAUCUUUCCCAUGUAAUAUUCUUGUUUCUUCUUAGUUUAGCCUCCUGAAUUUAUGCAGGCAAUGGGCUUGUUUGGUUUUCCUUUGUAUUACUUAUAAAAUGUAGUUUGUUCUGAUAACGUUCUUAUAAGAUUGAUGAUAUUAAUCUGUAUAUAUGCAUAUUUGUUUCUCUCCUGUUAUAUAUAUGUCCUUUAAAAAUUGGACACCAGAAACUAUGUAGCCUCAUUGUUUUACUCAUCCCCUUCAUUUAUUCAGUCCACUGACAGUAAGUUCCUAAUGUAUGUCAGGCCCUGAGAAAUCAAAUAUUGAUAUUACUUUUUACUACUAGAGUUACUACUUUCACAGGAAAUGUCUGCUGCAUUUUCUUAUUAGAAUUAUUGACAUCUAUAGAAUUAAAAAAUACAUCUUUUGCUUUUUUGUCUCCCAUCCAUAUUGUCAAGUACUGUUUCCUUUUAAAUGUACAUGUGGGGCUGGGCGCUGUGGCUCAUGCCUGUAAUCCCCGCACUUUGGGAGACUGAGGUGGGUGGAUCACUCAAGCCCAGAAGUUUGAGACCAGCCUGGCCAACGUGGUGAAACGUCGUCUGUAUUAAAAAUACAAAAAAAUUAGCUGAGCUUGGUGGCGCACACCUGUAAUCCCAGCUACUUGGGAGGCUGAGGCAUGAGAAUCGCUUGAGCUUUGGAGGCAGAGGUUGCAGUGAGCUGAGAUCAUGCCACUGUACUCCAGCAUGGACAACAGAGCAAGACUCCAUCUCAAAAAAAAAAAAAAAAAAAAAAUCUACAUGUGGUAUUAAAGUAGACUCAGGUUUGAAUUCUGACUCUCCCAUGUAUUAGCUGUGUAACAGAUAAAUCACUUAAUCUUUUUGGGUCUUGAGUUCUCAUCUGAAAAACAUAUUUAAUACCUACUUUAUAGGAUUUAAUUGAGAGAAUUGAGGUGCUAAAAAUGAAGUGAGAGAAUGUACAUACAUGUGUUGUAUAAACUUCUUAAAUUUAAAAAGUUAUAUGAUGGUAGUAUUUUUAUAAGGAUUGCUAUUCACAUAUUUAUCCUUGCACUCUGUUUGAAAUAUAAUUGUAGUUAUCCUUGGGAGCAAGAACUAAUUGUAUCAUGUUGAUCCUUAAACAUUGCAGCUGGUAAAUAGCAAAGACUCCUACUUUUUGGAUUGAAUUUCUUCAGAAAAUGGACUUAGAACAAGUGUUAAGGUGUAUGUGGAAUUUGAUGAUCUUGAAUGGGAUAAACGAGAGUGGGUUAAAGUUUAUGAAGAUUUUUCAACUUUCUUGGUGGAAUACCACUUAAUCUGGGCCAAAAGGAAUGACCCUAGCCAGACUCAGGGAUCAAAGAGCAAACAGAUUCAGUGGCCUGCAUUGACUUUCAAACCUCUGGUUGAAAGAAAUAUACCCAGUUCAGUCACUGCAGUAGAAUUCCUUGUAGAUAAGCAACUGGAUUUUUUAACUGAAGAUAGUGCCUUUCAGCCCUACCAGGACGACAUAGACAGCCUAAACCCAGUUCUCAGGGACAACCCGCAGCUUCAUGAGGAAGUGAAAGUCUGGGUAAAGGAACAAAAGGUUCAGGAGAUUUUUAUGCAAGGUCCUUAUUCCUUAAAUGGAUACAGAGUGAGAGUAUAUAGACAAGACUCUGCCACCCAGUGGUUUACUGGCAUAAUUACUCAUCAUGAUCUCUUCACCCGCACCAUGAUCGUUAUGAAUGAUCAGGUACUAGAACCACAGAAUGUCGAUCCUUCUAUGGUUCAAAUGACCUUUCUAGAUGAUGUUGUUCACUCUUUGUUAAAAGGUGAAAAUAUUGGCAUUACAUCACGACGCAGGUCUCGUGCCAAUCAAAACGUCAACGCUGUUCACAGCCAUUAUACACGUGCCCAAGCAAAUAGUCCCAGACCAGCAAUGAACUCCCAAGCUGCUGUACCAAAACAGAAUACACACCAGCAACAGCAACAAAGAAGUAUCCGUCCAAAUAAGAGGAAGGGCUCAGAUAGCAGUAUACCAGAUGAAGAGAAGAUGAAGGAGGAAAAAUAUGAUUAUAUAUCACGAGGAGAAAAUCCUAAAGGUAAAAACAAACACUUGAUGAAUAAAAGAAGGAAACCUGAGGAGGAUGAAAAGAAACUAAAUAUGAAAAGACUUCGAACUGACAAUGUUUCAGACUUUUCUGAGAGCAGUGACUCAGAAAAUUCAAAUAAGAGAAUAAUAGAUAAUUCCUCAGAACAGAAGCCAGAGAAUGAAUUGAAAAAUAAAAAUACUUCAAAAAUAAAUGGAGAAGAAGGAAAACCCCAUAAUAAUGAGAAGGCAGGAGAAGAGACCCUAAAAAAUAGCCAGCCUCCCUGGGAUCAAAUACAGGAAGAUAAAAAACAUGAAGAAGCAGAGAAGCGGAAGUCUGUUGACACUCAGCUUCAAGAAGAUAUGAUUAUUCAUUCGUCAGAACAGUCCACAGUUUCUGAUCAUAAUUCUAAUGAUUUACUUCCUCAGGAAUGCAAUAUGGAUAAAACACAUACCAUGGAAUUGCUACCAAAGGAGAAGUUUGUAUCCAGACCACCCACACCAAAAUGUGUUAUUGAUAUUACAAAUGACACUAAUUUAGAAAAGGUGGCUCAGGAAAACUCAAGUACCUUUGGCCUUCAGACACUUCAGAAAAUGGAUCCUAAUGUUAGUGAUUCAAAACACUCUAUUGCAAAUGCAAAAUUCUUGGAAACAGCAAAAAAAGAUUCUGACCAGAGCUGGGUCAGUGAUGUAGUUAAAGUGGAUCUAACCCAAUCAAGUGUUACAAAUGCUUCUUCAGGAAAUGAUCACUUGAACAUGGAAAAAGAGAAGUAUGUCUCUUACAUUUCUCCUUUAAGUGCAGUUUCUGUCAUGGAAGAUAAGCUGCAUAAGCGAAGUCCACCUCCAGAGACUAUAAAAUCUAAACUUAAUACUUCAGUAGAUACUCACAAGAUAAAAUCCAGCCCAUCACCUGAAGUUGUUAAACCCAAAAUAACUCAUUCUCCUGAUUCUGUAAAGUCUAAGGCCACUUAUGUGAACAGCCAAGCUACUGGUGAAAGAAGAUUGGCAAAUAAGAUAGAACAUGAGCUAUCAAGAUGCAGUUUUCAUCCAAUUCCUACUCGAAGCAGUACAUUAGAAACUACAAAGAGUCCUCUUAUCAUUGAUAAAAAUGAGCAUUUUACAGUUUACAGAGAUCCUGCACUUAUUGGGUCAGAAACAGGAGCUAAUCAUAUUUCACCUUUCCUAAGCCAGCAUCCUUUUCCUCUUCACUCCUCAUCUCAUAGAACCUGUUUAAAUCCAGGUACCCAUCAUCCUGCCUUAACUCCUGCACCCCAUUUACUAGCCGGAUCAUCUAGUCAAACUCCAUUACCUACCAUUAACACUCAUCCUCUGACUAGUGGUCCACACCAUGCUGUUCAUCACCCUCAUUUACUUCCCACUGUGUUACCUGGAGUGCCUACUGCCUCCUUACUUGGUGGCCACCCACGACUAGAGAGUGCUCAUGCCAGCAGCUUGAGCCACUUAGCGCUAGCACACCAGCAACAACAACAGUUGUUACAGCACCAGUCACCUCAUCUUCUUGGACAAGCCCAUCCUUCUGCUUCAUAUAAUCAGCUUGGACUUUAUCCAAUUAUUUGGCAGUAUCCAAAUGGAACACAUGCAUACUCAGGACUUGGUUUGCCUUCUUCUAAGUGGGUUCACCCAGAAAAUGCAGUUAAUGCUGAAGCUUCAUUAAGGAGGAAUUCUCCCAGUCCUUGGCUACAUCAGCCCACCCCUGUGACCUCAGCAGAUGGUAUUGGAUUACUUAGUCACAUUCCUGUCAGACCUUCCAGUGCAGAGCCUCAUCGGCCUCUUAAAAUUACAGCCCAUUCCAGUCCACCAUUGACAAAAACUUUAGUAGAUCAUCAUAAGGAAGAAUUAGAAAGAAAAGCUUUUAUGGAACCAUUACGGUCUGUUGCAUCCACAUCAGCCAAAAAUGACCUGGAUCUAAAUAGGUCACAGACUGGAAAAGAUUGUCACUUACAUAGGCAUUUUGUGGAUCCAGUAUUAAAUCAGUUACAGAGGCCACCCCAGGAGACUGGAGAGAGGUUAAACAAAUACAAAGAGGAACACCGUCGAAUUCUUCAAGAAAGUAUUGAUGUUGCUCCCUUUACAACUAAAAUCAAGGGACUUGAGGGUGAGAGAGAGAAUUAUUCCAGAGUGGCAUCAUCAUCUUCCAGUCCUAAAAGCCAUAUCAUCAAACAAGAUAUGGAUGUAGAACGCUCAGUAUCAGAUCUUUAUAAAAUGAAGCACUCAGUGCCUCAGAGUUUACCCCAAAGUAACUAUUUCACUACAUUGUCUAAUAGUGUGGUCAAUGAACCACCAAGAUCAUACCCAUCCAAAGAAGUUUCAAAUAUUUACGGUGAUAAACAGAGUAAUGCCCUUGCAGCGGCAGCAGCUAAUCCUCAAACUCUGACUUCAUUUAUAACAUCUCUUUCAAAGCCUCCACCUUUGAUUAAACACCAACCAGAAAGUGAAGGUUUAGUAGGCAAGAUACCAGAACAUCUUCCACAUCAGAUUGCAUCUCACUCAGUAACAACCUUCAGAAAUGAUUGUAGGAGUCCUACCCAUUUGACAGUUUCUUCUACAAAUACACUCCGCAGUAUGCCUGCAUUACAUAGAGCACCAGUAUUUCACCCACCAAUCCAUCACAGCCUGGAAAGAAAGGAAGGCAGCUAUAGUAGUCUUUCCCCUCCAACUUUAACUCCGGUGAUGCCAGUAAAUGCUGGUGGUAAAGUUCAAGAAUCACAGAAGCCUCCAACUCUAAUACCCGAACCAAAAGACUCCCAGGCAAAUUUUAAGAGUUCUUCAGAACAGAGUUUGACGGAGAUGUGGAGACCUAAUAAUAACCUCAGCAAAGAGAAAACUGAAUGGCAUGUGGAGAAAAGCAGCGGAAAGUUACAGGCUGCUAUGGCAUCUGUCAUUGUGCGUCCAUCUUCUAGUACAAAAACUGAUAGUAUGCCAGCAAUGCAGUUAGCUUCUAAAGAUCGUGUUAGUGAAAGAUCUUCAGCUGGGGCACAUAAAACAGAUUGCCUCAAACUAGCAGAAGCCGGAGAAACUGGAAGAAUCAUUUUGCCAAAUGUGAAUUCAGACAGUGUUCACACAAAAUCUGAAAAAAACUUUCAGGCUGUCUCACAGGGCAGUGUUCCCAGUUCAGUCAUGUCUGCUGUAAAUACGAUGUGUAAUACCAAAACGGAUGUAAUCACAUCUGCUGCCGAUACUACCAGUGUUUCCAGCUGGGGUGGUUCAGAAGUAAUUUCCUCUUUAUCAAAUACCAUUUUGGCCUCUACAUCAUCAGAAUGUGUAUCUUCAAAAAGUGUCAGUCAGCCAGUGGCUCAAAAACAAGAAUGCAAGGUCAGCACCACAGCACCAGUUACAUUAGCCAGUAGUAAGACAGGAAGUGUUGUUCAACCCAGUUCUGGGUUCUCAGGCACAACUGAUUUUAUCCAUUUAAAAAAGCACAAGGCAGCAUUGGCUGCAGCUCAGUAUAAAAGUAGUAAUGCCAGUGAGACUGAACCUAAUGCUAUAAAAAAUCAGACACUUUCAGCCUCCCUUCCUCUGGAUAGCACUGUAAUCUGUAGUACAAUUAACAAAGCAAACUCUGUAGGAAAUGGGCAAGCUUCCCAGACAAGUCAACCAAACUACCAUACUAAACUGAAAAAGGCCUGGCUCACCAGACACUCAGAAGAAGAUAAAAAUACUAAUAAAAUGGAAAAUUCAGGGAAUUCUGUAUCAGAAAUUAUUAAGCCAUGUUCUGUCAACUUAAUAGCCUCUACAUCUAGUGAUAUACAAAAUAGUGUAGAUAGUAAGAUCAUAGUUGAUAAAUAUGUAAAAGAUGAUAAAGUCAACAGGAGAAAAGCCAAAAGAACUUAUGAAUCUGGCUCUGAAAGUGGAGACUCAGAUGAAAGUGAAAGCAAGUCAGAGCAAAGGACUAAAAGACAACCUAAGCCAACUUACAAAAAGAAGCAAAAUGAUUUGCAAAAGAGAAAAGGUGAAAUAGAAGAAGAUUUGAAACCCAAUGGAGUUCUCAGCAGGAGUGCCAAAGAAAGAAGUAAACUGAAGUUGCAAAGCAACAGUAAUACUGGCAUUCCUCGUUCAGUAUUGAAAGAUUGGCGUAAAGUCAAGAAGCUGAAGCAAACUGGGGAAUCCUUUUUACAGGAUGACUCCUGCUGUGAGAUAGGGCCUAAUUUACAAAAGUGUCGAGAAUGUAGACUUAUUCGCAGUAAAAAAGGAGAAGAACCAGCUCACUCACCAGUAUUUUGUAGAUUUUACUACUUUAGACGGUUGUCAUUUAGUAAAAACGGAGUAGUUAGAAUAGAUGGUUUCUCUUCUCCUGACCAAUAUGAUGAUGAAGCUAUGAGUUUGUGGACACAUGAAAAUUUUGAAGAUGAUGAACUAGAUAUAGAGACUUCUAAAUAUAUCUUGGAUAUAAUAGGUGAUAAGUUCUGUCAAUUAGUAACAUCUGAAAAAACAGCUUUGUCCUGGGUGAAAAAGGAUGCCAAAAUUGCCUGGAAAAGAGCAGUGAGAGGAGUCCGGGAGAUGUGUGAUGCAUGUGAAGCAACAUUGUUUAACAUUCACUGGGUCUGCCAAAAAUGUGGAUUUGUGGUCUGCUUAGAUUGUUACAAGGCAAAGGAAAGGAAGAGUUCUAGAGAUAAAGAACUAUAUGCUUGGAUGAAGUGUGUGAAGGGACAGCCUCAUGAUCACAAACAUUUAAUGCCAACCCAAAUUAUACCUGGUUCUGUUUUGACAGAUCUUCUAGAUGCCAUGCACACUCUUAGGGAAAAAUAUGGUAUUAAAUCCCAUUGUCAUUGUACUAACAAACAGAAUUUACAAGUUGGAAAUUUUCCUACAAUGAAUGGUGUAUCUCAAGUUUUACAGAAUGUUCUUAAUCACAGUAAUAAAAUUUCUCUGUGCAUGCCUGAGUCUCAGCAGCAAAAUACUCCUCCGAAGUCUGAGAAAAAUGGUGGCAGCAGCCCAGAGAGUGAUGUAGGCACAGAUAACAAGUUAACUCCUCCAGAAUCCCAGUCACCACUGCACUGGUUAGCAGAUCUUGCAGAGCAAAAAGCCAGAGAGGAAAAAAAAGAAAACAAAGAACUUACCCUUGAAAACCAAAUUAAAGAAGAAAGAGAACAAGACAACUCUGAAUCUCCAAAUGGCAGAACAUCACCUCUUGUGUCCCAGAAUAAUGAACAAGGCUCAACCUUACGGGAUUUGCUGACUACAACAGCUGGAAAGCUACGUGUGGGGUCUACAGAUGCUGGCAUUGCCUUUGCCCCAGUAUAUUCAAUGGGAGCCCCAAGUAGCAAAAGUGGACGGACUAUGCCUAACAUUCUUGAUGACAUAAUUGCUUCAGUUGUUGAAAACAAAAUUCCACCAAGUAAAACCUCCAAGAUAAAUGUAAAACCAGAGCUUAAAGAAGAGCCUGAAGAAAGCAUAAUAUCUGCAGUGGAUGAAAAUAAUAAAUUAUACAGUGAUAUACCACAUUCUUGGAUCUGUGAGAAGCAUAUUUUAUGGCUUAAGGAUUAUAAGAAUAGCAGUAAUUGGAAGCUUUUCAAAGAAUGUUGGAAACAAGGACAGCCUGCAGUGGUUUCUGGUGUGCAUAAGAAAAUGAACAUUAGCCUAUGGAAGGCGGAAUCAAUUAGUCUUGAUUUUGGAGACCACCAAGCUGAUCUCCUGAACUGCAAAGAUAGCAUCAUUUCAAAUGCCAAUGUUAAGGAAUUCUGGGAUGGUUUUGAAGAAGUUUCAAAACGGCAGAAAAACAAGAGUGGAGAAACAGUUGUUUUAAAAUUGAAAGACUGGCCUUCAGGAGAAGACUUCAAGACUAUGAUGCCAGCAAGAUACGAAGAUCUUUUAAAAAGUCUGCCAUUGCCAGAAUAUUGUAAUCCAGAAGGAAAAUUCAAUUUGGCCUCUCAUUUGCCAGGAUUUUUUGUACGUCCUGAUCUAGGACCCAGGUUGUGCAGUGCCUAUGGUGUAGUUGCUGCUAAAGAUCAUGAUAUAGGAACAACAAAUCUCCAUAUUGAAGUUUCUGAUGUUGUAAAUAUACUAGUUUAUGUUGGCAUAGCAAAAGGAAAUGGCAUUCUCUCAAAAGCAGGAAUUCUCAAGAAAUUUGAGGAAGAAGAUUUGGAUGACAUUUUAAGGAAAAGAUUGAAGGACUCAAGUGAAAUACCUGGUGCUCUGUGGCAUAUUUAUGCUGGGAAAGAUGUUGACAAGAUAAGGGAAUUUCUUCAAAAGAUUUCAAAAGAACAAGGCCUUGAAGUUCUACCAGAACAUGAUCCAAUACGUGACCAAAGUUGGUAUGUGAACAAAAAGCUCCGUCAAAGGCUGCUUGAAGAAUAUGGAGUCAGAACCUGUACUCUUAUUCAGUUCCUUGGUGAUGCUAUUGUUUUGCCAGCGGGAGCACUUCAUCAGGUUCAGAAUUUUCACAGCUGUAUUCAGGUAACUGAAGAUUUUGUGUCUCCAGAACAUCUUGUAGAGUCAUUUCAUUUAACACAGGAACUGAGACUUUUGAAGGAAGAAAUCAAUUAUGAUGAUAAACUACAGGUUAAAAAUAUUUUGUAUCAUGCAGUCAAAGAAAUGGUGAGAGCCUUGAAGAUACACGAGGAUGAAGUAGAGGAUAUGGAAGAAAAUUAAGUGUGAUCCAGUUUGAUAUUUUUAGGUUGUUGAACUGGGAUUACUUAACCUUGAAUGAUGAUAUGUAUGCACACUGACUUUAAGCUUCAUAAAACCAUCAGUGCCAAGAAAUUCUCUUUGUAGUAAUUACUUGUUACUGACACCACAGCAGUAUAGCAUAUGUCACAGCUCCUGUGAUUCAAUGUUAUAAAACAAGCAGAAUUUUAAAAGCAGCACUAUAUAGCUGUUUUGUAUUAUAGUGUAUAUGAUGUUUGUGAAAAUGCCAGAUUUAAAAUGAUGUAUUUAUUUUUGGUAAAAAAUAAAAAAUUCUAUGCUAUAUUGUUGAUCAAGUGUAAAUGUGACCUUGUACAGUUUACUAAAAUUACUGAUAUUUUUCACUACAUUGAGACAGUUACUGUGAGAAUAGGACACAAACACCAGCUAUUGCCUGCAUCUGGGAAAUUGCUGAAUCGCACAGCAGUCAUGUCAUAAUCAGAAAAUUACUGCCAAAUAAUUGUAAAAUUUGUAAAGUAUAAAGUAUAUAAAGUAGAUACUAAAUACAGACACUUCAAUAUUUUGUUGAAGCUAUUGACUGUACAAUUAAACAUUUUCAAAAGGUGUAAUUUAUUUAAAAUUGUCUCAUUUUGGUAAAAUUUAUGUGAACUUUUAAAGCUAAAUAUUAAACUUAAUAUGCUAUGUAAAUAUAUACAUAUAUACAUUUAAUGAUGUAUUUUUUUAAAACAUUGGCUUGCUUUUGUUAAAGUGCAAGUGUUACAUAUGGCUUUGUACAUUAAAGUUGAAAGGGGUUUUACAUUUUCCAUUAAAAGGACUUUAUCAAAAA